AAUCUUGAGCAGGGAUAAAUUGUCGUGCUUGAUGCAUAAGGAAAGGAGGAGGUUUAAGAAAGCCUUGAUGGGGUAGUAGAGUGGCAUUAUAGCCCAUUGAGAGGUGAUUGUUUUGAGGAUGGAUUUCCAGGCUGGAAAAGAAAUGAGAGGUUCUAAAAGGUGGGUUAAAGAUUUAUAUCCUACAUGGAAGUGGUCAUCAAAGGAGGAGAGGAUAGAGUAAGCUUGAGAGGCAGGGAGAAGGAGCUUUCCAUGAUCUAAAAACCAGUUGCCUUGAGUGGGAAGUGACUGGUAGUUUAAGGUUUCAGAAGGAGAGUAAUAGGAGUGAUAGAUGAGAAGGAGAAAUAUUGGCCACUGGGAGCAGAUACUGGGGAGUUUGCUGUUUCUUUGGCUGUUUUAUUGGCAUAGGUGUUUCCUUGGGCAAUGGGAUCAGAGGUUUUUUGGUGUCCUUUGCAGUGGAUUACUCUGGCUUUGGCUGGAAGGAGGGCAGCUUUAAGGAGGGCUUUAUUAAGGGGGCAUUGAUAAUAGAGGAUCCUUGUGUAGUGAGAAAACCUCUUUCUGCCCAGUUGACAGGGUGGCGGUGGAGGAUGUGAAGGGCGUAUUUAGAGUCAAUUAGAUAUUAACAUGCAGUCCUUUGCCAAGAGUUAGGGCAUGAGUUAGUGCUAUUAAUUCAGCUUGUUGAGAGGUUGUAAAUGGGGAGAGUGCAGCAGUUUCAGUGAUAGAUGAGUGAGACACAAUGGCCUAUCCAGCUUUUCCUGGUGUUAAUCAACUGGUUUUUGAAGAACUGCCAUCAAUAAACCAAGUGUGGUCUGGGUCAGGGACAGGAAAAAGGGAAAUAUGGGGAAAAGGAGAGGAGGCUAUGUGGAUUAAGGAAAUACAGUUGUGUGGAUUAGGAUUUGUAGUGGGUAGUAAGUGAGAGGCCGGGUUGAAGUCCUGUCCAAAGGCAAUGGUCCCCAUGAGAUUUUCAAUAAAGAGUGAAUAGAGCUGGAGGAGGUGGGGAGCCGAGAGUAUGUUUUAUAUGUGAAGAGGAAACUAAGUCUUGGAGGUUGUGAGUGCUAUAAAAGGUGAGUGGGGCAUAGCCUGUGAUUUUGAGAGACUCUAAGAGUAUAAGGGCUGUGGCUGCUGUGGCAUGCAGGCAUGACGGCCAGCCCAGGACUGUAAGAUUAAGCUGUUUGAAUACAAAGGCUACUGGUCACAGGCCUGGUUCCUGAGUAAGAAUUCCUACAGCGCAGCCCUGCGUUUUUGCUGUGUGGAGAGGAAGGAGGGUUGGGAGGAGUCGGGAAGCGCUUGAGUAGGGGUUGCCUCUAGGGCCUUUUUUAGAGUAAAAGGAGGGGCGAGGGAAGGAUUUAGGAUCUGUGGGUUCAGCUAAGUUUCCUUUUGUGAGUUUAUAGAGUGGUUUGGUUAGGAUGGCAAAACCUGGUAUCCAAAGGCAGAAGUAUCCAACAACGUCUAAGAAGGAGAGGAGUAGUUGUUUGGUGGUGGGGAUUGGAAUUUGGAGAUUAGCUGAAUACGGUCUGCUGGAAGUGCACACCUAUGUUGGUGGAGGAUUAUACCAAGAUAAGUAGAAAUUUGAGCUUUGGAGGGGGAUACUCUGUACCCCUUGGAGUAGAGGUGUUGAAGAAGCAGGAUAGUGUCUUGCUGGGAGGAUUGGUAAGAGGGGCUGCAAAGAAGAAGGUCAUCCACAUAUUGAAUGAGAUGGGAAACAAAUGGACGAAAAGAAAGCAGGUCACGGGAGAGGGCCUGGCUAAAGUAGUGUGGGCUGUCUCUGAAACCUUAGGGCAGGACGGUCCAGGUGAGUUGUUGGGACUGGUGGGUGUCAGGGUCAGUCCAAGUAAAGGCAAAAAGGGGCUGGGAAGAGGGAUGUAAGGGGAUGGUAAAGAAGGCAUCUUUGAGGUCAAUAACAGAAUAAUGAGUUGUGGAAGGCGGUAUUGAGGAUAGGAGAGUAUAAGGGUUAGGCAUGACAGGAUGAAUGGGGAGGACAAUCUGAUUGAUGAAACGAAGGUCUUGGACUAGCCUGUAGGAUUUAUCUGGUUUUUGAAUAGGUAGGAUGGGAGAGUUGUAAGGGGAGUUGGUAGGGACUAAGAGGCCAUGCUGUAGUAGACAGGUAAUAACAGGCUUUAGGCCCCUUAAAGUCUGUUGUGGGAUGGGGUAUUGGCAUUGAGCAGGAUAAGGGUGGCCAUGUUUCAAUGGGAUGAUAAGGGGUGAAUGAUCAGUUGCAGGCGAAGGAGUGGAGGUAUCCCAUACUUUAGGGUUAAGGUGGGGAGAUGAAAGGAGAGGUUGCGAGGGAGGUUUGGAAUUGGAUAAAAGGGUAGCUCUGAGAUGUGGCUGUAGUCCAGGAAUAGUCAGGGAGGAGGAUAAUUUAGUUAAAAUAUCUUGGUCUAAUAAGGGGACUGGGCAGGUGGGGAUAACUAGGAAGGAGCGCAUAAAGGAGUGUUGCCUGAUUUGGUACCAGAGUUGGGGAGUUUUAAGGGGUUUAGAAGCUUGGCCGUCAAUAUGCACAACAGUUGUGGGGGCAAGGGAAACAGGCCCUUGAAAAGAAGGUAACGUGGAGUGGGUAGCCCCCGUAUCGAUUAAGAAGGGGACGGACUUACCCUCCACUGUAAGAGUUACCCGAAGCUUGGCGUCUGUGAUGGUCCAGGGGGCCUCCGAGAUAUUCGGGCAACGUCAGUCUUCAGCCGCCAAGCCGAGGAGAUCUGGGAAGGAGUCGGUCAUUUCGGGUUUGUACUCCAGGAGCUCCAGGAUUGGUGAUGAGAGUCAGACAGUCUGACUUCCAGUGAGGGCCCACACAGGGGCAUGGCUUAGAAGGAAUCCCGGGCCGUGGGCAUUCCUUGGCCCAGUGGCCAGGUUUUUGACAUUUGAAGCAAGGUCCCAGAGGGGCAGUUAAACGCUGCGGUUUGUACGCCUUGAAGUUUUUGCAGGUAGGCGGUGCUGCUGGGGUUUGUUUUAAGGUGGAGGCAAGCAUUUGUCAUUCUGAAAGGCGCGCUGCCGCCUGGCAGCCUCUUCCCUAUUAUUGAACACCUUGAAGGCAGGGUUGAUUAAUUCCUGUUAUAGGGUUUGAGGGCCAGACUCUAAUUUUUGAAGUUUCUUUCUAAUAUUAGGAGCUGACUGGGUAAUAAAAUGCAUGUUAAGAAUAAGGCGGCCUUCUGUCCCUUCAGGGUUUGGUGCUGUAUAUCGCCUGAGGGUGGCAGCUAGAUGGGCCAUAAACUGAGCUGGGUUUUCACCUUUGUUCUCAGUGGUCUCCUUUAGUUUGUCAUAAUUCACGGCUUUAUAUGCAGCUUUCUGAAGCCCUUGAACUAAACAAGAGAUCAUGUAGUCCUGCCUGGCUAUGCCUUGGGCCCCUGCCUGGUAGGUCCUUUGGGGCCUUCACGGGUACUGCCCUAGUGCCUGGCCUUGGAGGCCAGGCUCAAGGCGCCAGCAGUCAUCAGCAUAAGAUUGAGCUAGGGUCCAAAGUGAAGAUGACAUUUAAGUCAUUCCAAGUGGGAUUAUAGGACUGUGUUAAGUAUUGGAAUUCUUGUAUAUAUUUGAGUAGGGUCUGACGGAAAAGAGCCUGAAUGCUGACUGAUUUGGGAAAGGUCAGAUAUAGAGAAAGGGAUGUGAACCUGGACUUUUCCUUCGGCUCCUGCCACCUCUCAAAGGGGAAAUUGCUGGGCAGGGGCAUGGGGGUCGGCUUCAGGGUCAAAUUGUAAGCCAGAGCAGGUGUGAGGAGGGAUGGUAAUGGGAGGGACGUAAAGGGGUGGCUUGUGGGUAGAACUCGGUUCUGAGGGGGAAUUAGGGCCAGGUUCGGAUAGGUGGGUUGGGGGGAGAAAGAUUGAAGGGGUUAACAGGUAAAGAGGAGUCAGCAUCCCCAGUGGAAGAAGGAGAGGUAGAUGGAAGGGAGAUAAGGAAAAUUUGGGAUGGACCACAUUGGGAGCAGAGACUAGGGAGAGAUCAUAGUAAAAAAUGCCUGGAUGUAGGGUACCUCAGACCAUUUGCCCAUUUUGCAACCGAAGUUGUCUAAGUCCCGCAAAAUAGAGAAAUUGAAAGUGCUGUUUUCUGUCCGCUGAGAGCCAUUGUCUAAUUUAUAUUGGGGCCAGGCCGUGUUACAGAAAAAAAAAAUUAGACGUUUAGGCUUUAGAUUGGGUGAAAGCUAAGAGGUUUGAGGUUUUUGAGGACAGAAGCCAGUGGGGAAGAUGGAGGGUGGGAGGUUGCCCAUGUUAGAACUGGGAAAGUUUGAGGGGAAAGAAAGAGACAAGGAAAAGAGCAACCACUAGCAUCCUCAGUGGGCAUCCCCAAUGGAGGUCCCGGGUUGUGUGGCUGGCGAAUGGCCAAGGCUGGCAUCCCUGGCAUUCACCAAACACUGAGGGAAGACUGUCUUCCCAAGAAGAGUCCGUGACCAACGUUGGAUUUUGGAAACAUGGAUAAGAGGAAGGUUCCUUGUCUCAAUUUUGAGGAGAGAAAAAGAGGGAGAGAGAUGAGGAGAGACCGAGGCAGCUUACCCGAUCCGUAGACAGAGGUGGGAGUGUUCGCGGGGGCUGGUCUGAGGUCCUGAGGUCGAGGGAAGUCUCUUUGAUGGAAGAGCGUGGGGAGGAUAGGGGAGAGGUCUCCCAGAGAGAGUUCCCCUAUCCCGGGCUUUCGGCACCGAAUGUUAUGCAUGCGUCCAAUUGAAGAGACAACCUGAACAGGCUAAGUGUGAGCAACAAGGCUGUUUAUUCACUCGCGUGCAAGUGAGCUAAGUAUGAAAAGGGAGUCAGCAGAGGGUGGUGGGAUUGGAGAUGGUUUUAUAGGUUAGGGGUAGGCAAUGGAAAGUUACAGUUAGGGGCUGGAUUUUGCAGGUAGGGGAAGAAUGUCACAAGGUACAUUAUCACAAGGUUACAGAGCACAGUGUCAUGUGUCAUGAGGUUGAUUGAUCAGUUAGGGUAGAGCCUGUUACAAUGGUAGAAUGCCCCAAGGCUGGCUAAUCAGCUAAGACAGGUACUAGCCGUUUUUCUUCUUUUGUGGUUUUCCUGUUGUCCCAGAUUUUCUGGCUGCAGGACACCUUCUGGAUGUGUACGUGUGGGUCACAGGGGUCACGAUGGCUUGACCAUGGCGCAGCUUGGUCAGGGGACCUUACAAUUUGGUCAUAAAAUUCCUAGAUCUGCCACUUCCUCUUACCAGUCAUGGGAUCAUGGUUUUCUCAGGUGUAAGUGGGAACAAUCAUUGCUUGCAUGGCUUUAGAACACUUUGCUAAGGAUCACAUAAGAUACCGCAUGUGAAAACAUGAAAAACAUUUGGCUCUGUAUGUUCCAGUGAGUACCUAAGGGCUAUCACUUAUACUCUUAAGAAGAAAAAUUGUGCAUGUCUCUAGGGAUAUUUUUGUGUGUGUGUUGUUGUGGUUGAGACGGAGUUUCACUCUUGUUGCCCAAGCUGGAGUGCGAUGGCGUGAUCUUGGCUCACUGCAACCUCCGCCUCCUGGGUUCAGGCGAUUCUCCUGCCUCAGCCUCCCAGGUAGCUGGGAUUACAGGCAUGCGCCACCAUGCCCAACUAAUUUUUUUUUUUUUUUUUUUUUUUAGUAGAGAUAGGGUUUCUCCGUUUUGGUCAGGCUGGUCCCAAACUCCUGACCUCAGGUGAUCCUCCUGCCUCGGCCUCCCGAAGUGCUGGGAUUACAGGUGUGAGCCGCCACACCUGGCCUCUAGGGAUUUUUUUUUUUUUAAGGACAGUAUGUAUGCAAAAAUAUGAAGGCCUUAAGAGAAAAUGUAGUUUGUUUCUAAACGUCCUAAAGUCAGCUAUUUUAUGGUGUUCUCUCUGGAAAACAACCAGGAAGGCCGUAAUCUCUCCUCCUUGUAAGUGAGAAGCUGAACAAGUGGCUCUUAUUGGAAGAUAGUCUUAACAAUUCAGAAUUCACAUAGCUUUAUUAGAAGAUUGCCUAAGUGUGACCAGGUUUUUGCUUUUAAAAUAAAACCUUUUCUUUUAUUCUACAAGUAUUAAUGUAAUUAAACAAACUCUUAAAUAGCAUAUUGCUUGUUCCAUGCCAGGCAGUGUUCUAAGUGUUUUAUCAGCAUUAACUUGUGCAGUCAUCCUACUAACCCUUGAGGAAGGUAGGACUAUCCCCCCUAUUUGACAGAGGAAGGCACCAAGGCUGCCCAGGGCUGAACCCCCAGACCUAACUACAAUCUGAGCUCUGUGAUGACCGAGAUAGUGAGGCCUCCUGUCCCUGAGGUUCUGGUGAGGGAGCCAGACAGGCAGAUAAGCAAGUGCAAGAAAGUGCUGAGGGCUGUGAGGUGUGCGGAGGCAUUCUAGGACACCUCCCUCUAUGGUCACUUCUCUGCCGUGUUUAAUACUAACAGUGAAUUGUAGAAUAUAGUACUUUAGUUUUAUUCCAUGCAAAUCUACAGCUCCAGUUAGUGAAAUGGAUCAUACACACAGAAGAUAUGGACAUCAAAAGUUGAAGAAAAAUGUUCAUUUGGAUUUGGAAGACCGCCUGGCAAAAUUUAUGAAGACAGAAGAAGCCAUUAUAUACUCAUAUGGAUUUGCCACCAUAGCCAGUGCUAUUCCUGCUUACUCUAAAAGAGGGGACAUUGUUUUUGUAGAUAGAGCUGCCUGCUUUGCUAUUCAGAAAGGAUUACAGGCAUCCCGUAGUGACAUUAAGUUAUUUAAGCAUAAUGACAUGGCUGACCUCGAGCGACUACUAAAAGAACAAGAGAUCGAAGAUCAAAAGAAUCCUCGCAAGGCUCGUGUAACUCGGCGUUUCAUUGUAGUAGAAGGAUUGUAUAUGAAUACUGGAACUAUUUGUCCUCUUCCAGAAUUGGUUAAGUUAAAAUACAAAUACAAAGCAAGAAUCUUCCUGGAGGAAAGCCUUUCAUUUGGAGUCCUAGGAGAGCAUGGCCGAGGAGUCACUGAACACUAUGGAAUCAAUAUUGAUGAUAUUGAUCUUAUCAGUGCCAACAUGGAGAAUGCACUUGCUUCUAUUGGAGGUUUCUGCUGUGGCAGGUCUUUUGUAAUUGACCAUCAGCGACUUUCCGGCCAGGGAUACUGCUUUUCAGCUUCGUUACCUCCCCUGUUAGCUGCUGCAGCAAUUGAGGCCCUCAACAUCAUGGAAGAGAAUCCAGGUAUUUUUGCAGUGUUGAAGGAAAAGUGCGGACAAAUUCAUAAAGCUUUACAAGGCAUUUCUGGAUUAAAAGUGGUGGGGGAGUCCCUUUCUCCAGCCUUUCACCUACAACUGGAAGAGAGCACUGGGUCUCGCGAGCAAGAUGUCAGACUGCUUCAGGAAAUUGUAGAUCAAUGCAUGAACAGAAGUAUUGCAUUAACUCAGGCGCGCUACUUGGAGAAAGAAGAGAAGUGUCUCCCUCCUCCCAGCAUUCGGGUUGUGGUCACGGUGGAACAAACAGAGGAAGAACUGGAGAGAGCUGCGUCCACCAUCAAGGAGGUAGCCCAGGCCGUCCUGCUCUAGGCAGAGUCCCGGGACCAUGGCCUCCUGCCACACAACACGCAGAGAGGACUCAAGACUCCCGCUGGCCAUGGAGUGGCCUGAAAGAGAGCAAGAACAUGUGGAUCUUUGAUAGGAUUGUUACCAAAUGGUGUCAGUAUGGACCAAUUGUGUGACCAUGAGAAGGAUGCUUAUUUUUUUUAAAAAGAAAACACAUCUAAAAGCCCAGGAACUGAUUUUUUUAAGAGGAAAACUAAUGACAGUGUAUAACUGAUGUUUAAAUUGUGCAUUUAGUACUAUUUAAAUGUUUUCUUAUACUAGUAUUUUAUAUUCUUUUGUUGUCGUUUAAAACUGGAGCUUCAGUGUCUCUUCCCUCCCUCUAAUAGUAAUGGUUCAGUAAGCACUCCUUAACUCCUUAGUAUUUCAUAGAAAAAUGACUGCAACAUUAAAGCUAAGAGGAACACUUCAACAUAUGUGGUACAAAUUUAUAUUGAAGAUCUAAAUAAACCACGUAUUUUCCAGUCUUCGUUGUGUGAAGCUAAAUGGUGGCUAAAAGGAACACUUUUUGUGUGAUUAUUAUAAACUUUGCAUUGUAUUUGAAUCUUAGAACUUUUGUACACACUAAAUAUUGAUGUCACACCAUUUCUAAUCUGAGCAUCCUUAGCCAGAGAAUAUUCAUUAUACUUCCUAAGUGAGCAAUAAUUUAAAUCAGAAGCUAUUUUAUUUUAAUGUAAUUAACCUUUCUUUACAUUUCUUAUGUGUUCACCUCUAAUCUGUUUUAGGAAGAGAGUUGGUUAUUAUGUUGAUCCCAUAAUAUAAAUCAUAUCCUUUAUAUUUUAGAAUAUCUCAAAUGUAUUCCUUUUUUGUAUGGUGGGUUUGCCUAGGGACGUGUAACUACAGGCUUUUACUAAGCCAAGGAAAAAGAGAAUUUUUCUUUUCAUCUUACAAAUUCCAGAUAUCUACAAAAGAUGUGAAAGCACUAAAAAUACCAUUUUUAAGCAGUACUUUACCUGUUUUUUCUUUAGCAAACCAGGUUAUGUGGUGUAAAGGUUUGUUAUACGUGCCACAAUAUAGCAUAUAAAUAUUAUGCCAUCAUUCCUUCUCUUGUUAAAGGUAGAAGAAUAAAAUUGUGAUUUUUAUAACCUGUGCUUAUUACUCAAAUGGUCUUCAACAUCUUUUUAAACAACACAUACUUUUUGAAUGUUCAGUUUCUAUUUUGCUUGAGGUAUUUUGUACAUAUGUGCCUUGUGAUUGCUGCUGCUUUAAAGGAUAAAGUACUCUUUGGGGGAUGAGUCUGGUUUGUUUUGUUUUAUUUUUUAAUGAAAUAAACCUAUAUUCCUGA